GUAGCUAGGAGCGGACGCCAUAGGUGCAUUGUGGGAAGCACUUUGCUGUCCACAGCCAGGCCGCUUGUGAUGAAACUGUAACUUACAAGAAAAGGGCUGGGUUUUGAAAAUAACACAGGCUCUAAAAACCCUAAGAAGCGGUGCAACUUUUGGCAGGAAUCGGGGUUAGCGGGACCUCAAGGGCUCACUGCGGCUAAGUGAACGCUGACUGGUCCUCCAGCGUGAGCUAGAACAGACGUCUCUAUGGUCAAGUAAACAGAGCGUGUGCUGUCUUCCCCAUGUGGUGGGGUUGCGCAUGAUCAGUAGCUGCACCACUAGAAAGAUGGCGGAGCAAGAGCAAAGAAAAAUCCCUUUGGUUCCAGAAAAUCUCCUGAAAAAGAGGAAGGCUUAUCAAGCCCUCAAAGCCACCCAGGCAAAGCAGGCACUUUUGGCAAAGAAGGAGCAGAAGAAAGGAAAAGGGCUCAGGUUUAAGCGACUGGAAUCAUUCCUACAUGAUUCCUGGCGGCAGAAACGUGACAAGGUGCGUCUCAGACGACUAGAAGUGAAACCUCAUGCCUUGGAAUUGCCAGAUAAACAUUCCUUGGCCUUUGUUGUACGCAUCGAAAGGAUUGACGGCGUGAGUUUACUGGUGCAGAGAACCAUUGCAAGACUUCGCCUAAAGAAAAUUUUUAGUGGUGUCUUUGUAAAAGUCACCCCCCAGAAUCUAAAAAUGCUGCGUAUAGUGGAACCUUAUGUGACCUGGGGAUUUCCAAAUCUGAAGUCUGUCCGAGAACUCAUUUUGAAACGUGGACAAGCCAAGGUCAAGAAUAAGACCAUCCCUCUGACAGACAAUACAGUGAUUGAGGAGCACCUGGGGAAGUUUGGCGUCAUUUGCUUGGAAGACCUCAUUCAUGAAAUUGCCUUCCCAGGGAAGCAUUUCCAGGAGAUCUCAUGGUUCUUGUGCCCUUUCCACCUCUCAGUGGCCCGUCAUGCUACCAAAAAUAGAGUGGGCUUCCUCAAGGAGAUGGGCACACCUGGCUAUCGGGGUGAACGCAUCAAUCAGCUCAUCCGUCAGCUGAACUAGACCCAGGUGAGGCAGGGCUGAAAACUGCCCUUGGGCUGACUUUUGAUAGGCCAUGCCUUGCCACUUUACAAGUUCUUUUUGCAUUUACUAGUAUUUAAGAGUAACCUUGAGAUUGGGAGGAAUAGAGGAGGCUGGUACAAAUAGAUGGAGACCUGCUGGGAUCAGUGAAUGCCUGAUUAGGACAUGGGGCUAUGCAUAGCCUAAGAGUUAUAGGCUUAAAGAUGUCGAGUAACUAAAAACUGUAUUGCUGGCCGGGCGCGGUGGCUCACGCCUGUAAUCCCAGCACUUUGGGAGGCCAAGGCGGGCAGACCAUGAGGUCAGGAGAUUGAGACCAUCCUGGCCAACAUGGUGAAACCCUGUCUCUACUAAAAAUACAAAAAUGAGCUGGGUGUGGUGGCGCGUGCCUGUAGUCCCAGCUACUCGAGAGGCUAAGGCAGGAAAAUCGCUUGAACCCAGGAGGCAGAGAUUGCAGUGAGCCAAGAUUGCACCAGUGCACUCCAGCUGGGCGACAGAGCGAGACUCCAUCUCGGAAAAAAAAAAAAAAAAACUAUUGCUGCAGUCAUUCAGAUGGAAAUGAGGAAAGAAUAAUAUUAAUAACUGAUUUCAAAAAGGACUUGAAGAUGUGAAUCAUCUAUUUUGCUGAAGAAAUCUUAACUCUUUGAAAUUACUUUUUAUUGCUGUUGUCAUACUCUUAGGUGCCAAACUGCGGUAAAUUUUUUAUCAGUGAAGUGGAAGCAUGUGUUUUGUUUUGGAAAUUUUUAUCAAGUAUCUUCAGAGAAGAUUAUUUCCUGCUUUAUCUUCAGAAACUGGAAAGGGUCAAAGAAAAGACAGUAGCUGGCCGGUCGUGGUGGCUCAUGCCUGUAAUCCCAACACUUAGGGAGGCUGAGGUGGGCAGAUCACCUGAGGUUGGGAGUUCGAGACCAGCCUGACCAACAUGGAGAAAUGCCAUCUCUACUAAAAAUACAAAAAUUAGCCGGGCAUGGUGGCACGUGCCUGUAAUCCCAGCUACUCAGGAGGCUGAGGCAGGAGAAUCGCUUGAACCUGGGAGGUGGAAGUUGCAGUGAGCUGAGAUCACGCCAUUGCACUCCAGCCUGGGCAACAAGCGAAACUCUGUCUCAAAAAAAAAGAAAAGACAGUAGCAUAUGUUCAUGUCAAGCACCUCUCAUCACAGUCGAGUUCCAAGGAAAAAUUCCAGUGUUUUCUGCAUUGGGUGCUGUGUCAUCUGAAAUCGGCACAUUCCAUGGAGGAAGGAGUCCUGCUUUGUUGCAUGUAUCCUAGGGUUUAAUGUUGGUAAAUGAGUCACUCUAGCAUUUGUAGAAGGCUCCCUGAGACUCCUGCAGCAGUCGACCAAGCCCAAGGACAUAAUUGAAUCUGGAGAGUCCUGGGGCCUUGUUUUGAAAAAGACUUGAAAUACACAUAGGAAGAAAGGCAUAAAAAUAAAUGUUCACUUGUCUCUGCUGUGAGUAUGUGUUCCAACUUUUCAGUGAUGGCUUUGAGAAUUCUCAAACUUGACUGGCUCUAAGUGUAUCUGGUGGCUUUUGUAUCGUAACCUGAAACUGGCUUAGUACUUUUUCCUAAAAGCUCAGGAUUUGAGAAUGAGGACCCCUUCGCCAGGAAAACAUGUAUACACUCAAAAUUUUGCUUGCAGUUCUAGGGUGUUUAGACCCUUCUCAGAUACCUGUGCAUCUUAUGGGUUUUGUUUUUCUCUUUGAGACAGUCUCACCCUGUUGCCCAGGCUGGAGCGCAGUGGCAUGAUCUCAGCUCAUUGCAGCCUCCACCUCCUGGGUUCAAGUGAUUCUGCCUCAGCCCCUUGAUCAGCUGGGAUUACAUGCAUGUACCACCACACCCAGCUAAUUCUUGUAUUUUUAGUAGAGAUGGAGACAGAGUUUCACCAUGUAGGCCAGGCUAGUCUCAAACUCCUGACCUCAAGUGAUCCACAAGCCUGGGCCUCCCAAAGUGCUGGGAUUACAGGCAUGAGCAACUGCGCCCAGCUCUUGUGUACCUUAUGUGAGGAAGUCCUGCUCAAUCAGGAUCGGUCACGCAGGCCCUGAUCUUGCUACUCUGGUUCCAUGUCCUAUGGAAGACCAAAGUUUACCAAGAUAGAUUUUUCCCUUCAUAGUGGCAGAUAGUGUUAACCCCUGCACCAUCUGUAACUCAGAAAUCCCCACCAUUUCUUCCCCUGGGCUUCAGAAUAGAAUUGCCUGGUUUCUCUGAUGAUCAGCAUGGUUCCUUAAAACCCAAAUCAGCAAGGAAUGAACAAUUUUGUUUGGCAUGGAUGAAAUUAGCACUGUUUGGCUCGUUAGGCCCCAGGCAGGCAGGCACCUUAAUUUUUUCCUUGCAUAUUCUAGUCUUCAGAAGCAUUGCCUUUUGUCCUACUGGUAGUGACAUAGACCAAUAACAGGGCAUCUGGGGAUUUUAAUCCUGAAAACAGUGAGUCUGAUACUGCUUGUGUUUUUCAUCAGUGUCCACCCCAAGUGGGUCUUCCUGCUAUUCUCUUCACUUAGUUGCCCCUCACUUGCCAUCUGAGCAAUUGGCAAGGAUGUGCCAGGCCUAGGUUAAACUUGGAAACAUGCUUGACCAUUCUAUUCCCUGGUCCUUUAAGAUCAGUUUGGCUGCAAUUUUGGCUCCUUGGACCCUCAAGCAUAGCUGGUAAAUCAAGUUAGAGAUGUAACUGCCUUAAAACAUGCCAGCUUAGGCUGGGCACGGUGGCUCACACCUGUAAUCUCAACACUUCAGGAGGCUGAGGCAGGCAGAUCACUUGAGGUCAGGAGUUCGAGACCAGCCUGACCAACAUGGAGAAAUUCUGUCCCUACUGAAAAUACAAAAUUAGCCGGAUGUGGUGGUGCAUGCCUGUAAUCCCAGCUACUUGGGAGGCUGAGGCAAGAGAAUUGCUUGAACCCAGGGAGGCAGAGGUUGCAGUGAGCCGAGAUCACACCAUUGCACUCCACCUUGGGCAACAAAAGCAAAACUCUGUCUCAAAAAAAAAAAAAAAAAAAGUGCCAGCGUAUGAGGUAAUUAGAUUGGUUCUCUCCAGAGGUAACCUGCCAAGAAGAGAUGCUAUAGAUGUUACUCCUAUACUGUAAAACAUUGUGAAAUCAGAUUACUUUAAAAUGAUGUAUUACAAAGUUAUGCAAAAAAGCAGUUGUGACUAUGGAAGCCCAAGGCUUAUAUCCCAGCUCUGUCUUACACUAAAUAUGGGUACAGUGUUUCCACUCUGUCCAUAAAAUGGGAGCUAAUAUUCUCCAACCUGUGUGCCUGACAUGAUGGUUAAAGGGAUUAAACAAAACAAUAGUUUGUAAUUUAUUCUGUCAGAGCAAACUGCUGGUAAAUAAAAGGGACUAAGUUGACGAAAAAUAAAUUUUAAAAAACCUAAUAAAACAAGUUUGUAAUUUAUAAUUGUAUACAAAUAAAAGAUGUUACAAAAAUUGCGCACUUA